AACAGGAUCGGGUGGGGGGGUGGGAUGCGGGUGGGGGAAAACUGGGGUUGCCAAAGCCGCCUCUCCGCCUUCAGUCCGCCCCUCCAGUCCGCCGCUCCCGGCGCCCCUGCCGCCGCGCCCGCCCAGCGACCCCAUGACACAGAUCGGCUUAAAGCUCCCCGCCUGUCCGCCUGCCCUCGAGAGAGGGUCCCGACCCCCAGACAGGUCUCCGAAGGCUGGGCUUCGCCUCACGCCGACCUCCGGCCCCACCCCACCCGCGUAACUAUAAACUCCAGCUACUUGCCGCGCUGCUUUUGCACAGACUCAUGCCCUGCCCCAGAAGGGACAGUGGCCGUGCUGUGGCGGGAACAGCGGGCGGGCUGGUCCAGAGCAGGGCCUGCCUGGGUGAGGAGGAUUUGGAGGGCCAGGCCCUGUCGUCACAGGGUUAUGAGGCCGAAGGGACCAUUCCAUUUACAACUGCGCUGAAGAAUUGUGCUAAGUGAAAUAAGCCAGAUACAGAAAGACAAAUACUGUGUGAUCUCGUAUAUGGAACCUAUAAAAGCGUUGAACCAUAGAAACGGCAGAACAGACCAGGCGCUGUGGUUCACGCCUGUAAUCCCAGCACUUUGGGAGGCCGAGGCGGGUGGAUCACUUGAGGGGAAAUGGUGUCCUGCUGGAGGGAGAACUGAUCGAUGUAUCUCGGCACAGCAUCUUGGACACUCAUGGCAGGAAGGAGCGCUACUACGUGCUGUAUAUCCGGCCCAGUCACAUCCAUCGCCGUAAAUUCGACGCCAAGGGAAAUGAAAUCGAGCCCAACUUCAGCGCCACCAGGAAGGUGAACACGGGCUUCCUCAUGUCGUCCUACAAGGUGGAAGCCAAGGGGGACACUGACAGGCUCACGCCCGAGGCGCUGAAGGGGCUGGUCAACAAGCCAGAGCUGCUCGCGCUGACAGAGAGCCUCACCCCCGACCACACAGUGGCGUUCUGGAUGCCCGAGUCAGAGAUGGAGGUGAUGGAACUCGAGCUGGGGGCCGGGGUACGGCUGAAGACUCGGGGCGAUGGUCCCUUCCUGGAUUCAUUGGCCAAACUUGAGGCUGGAACAGUGACCAAGUGUAAUUUCACUGGUGAUGGAAAGACAGGGGCAUCCUGGACAGACAACAUCAUGGCCCAAAAGUGUUCGAAGGGGGCUGCAGCGGAGAUCCGAGAGCAGGGGGAUGGGGCAGAGGACGAGGAGUGGGAUGACUGAGGGACGUGGCUGCCUCUGGGGGCACCAGCACCUUCUGUAGCAUUGUGGAACAUUUCUUCCAUGAACUUCUACUCUGGAGCUGGAGAGAACAGUCUGCCAAGUCUUACCUGGUUCUUCCCCAUAGCCACCUUGGAAUACUCUUUGAACAAGCUCUGCUAAAACCAAACCCAUGACCACUGUGUUGGUGGUGGGGCCUCAUGCUGUGGCUCAGGGAGGGCCCCUCCCUGCAUGUGAGUCUAGCCUUCCUAGACAUUACAUGAUGACCCUUUAAAAAAAAAUUAGAGAUGGAGGUCUCACUAUGUUGCCCAGGCUGAUCUCAAACUCCUGGACUCAAGCGAUCCACCCCCCUCCACCUCCCAAGGUGUUGGGAUUACAGGCGUGAGCCACUGCACCCAGCCUCAUGUUGACCCUGGCCCUGGAUAGCAGCUUUGUUUGUAGAGGCAGGUGGUGGGAGAGACCCUAGGACAGCCUGAGAGUAACUGGACCUGGUAUUGGUGCGGAGUGGGGAAUAUCCCUUGUCUAAAUGCAGAGCAGCUGAGAGAAGUUAGCGGGGCUCUUCCUCCGUUCUCAUUGUUUCCUGCUUUCCUUCCCCACCCACCCCUUCCUCAGCACUCUGUGUUGUAGCCUGUACUAUCCUGCUUCAAGCCUCCGUGUCCCUUGUACCUUCCCCCUACCUUGAGUUGCCAGUUCUUUACUCCCUCAAAUGUUCCCAUGCCACCUCUGGGGUUUCUGUUAUCUGACAUCCCUGGCUGCUUUCCUGGUAGAUGCCAUUCCCAGAGAGGCCAACAGCGUUCCCAGGCGUGGCUGGCUGGUCCGCAUCUCUCAGACUCACUCUGCCAGGCUACAGUUUUGAGAAUACCUUUUUUGUUGUUGUUUUGUACCUGGAGAACUUUUUAUGAAUGAGUAAAUCUUCAGAAAGGAAUUCCUCCACCCUUACUGGGUUAUUGUCAGGUGUAAACGGCCUUUCAGCUGAGCAAUGUUCCUAUGAGAAGGAAGCCAUUUCUCUUGGCUCAUGAACACUGCCUUUUGGGUAGUAUACCCACACCCAGAUCUGUGAAGAGACCUGGAAUUGAAGUCUCCAUGUCGUCAGGACUUGGUGGCAUGUGGAUCUUGCUUGACUUGGGAAAAGAGAGGGUGGUGGUGAACUAAUAAUUAUGGAGUCCCCCUAAUGUGUCGAACACAAUGCUAGAUGAUUUCCAUGAUAAUAAUUACUCAUACUUGUGCUAAGCACUUGCGAUAUCGUACUUCUCACAACAGUCCAUGAGGUACUGAUUAUUAUUCCCAUUUUCUCAUGAGACUAAAGCUCAGAGCUCUAGGAUAGUAUACAGUGGCAAGAGGAAUUUACAUCCAAGCACUCAGAUUUCAAAGCCCACAUUCUUAACUACCGGACUAUUCAUAUUACAGAGCAGGAAAAGGGUCUCAGACAGGUUAAGCAACCUGCCCAGAGUCACACAGCUAAUGAGUAGCAGAAUCAGGAUUCAAACCCAGAGCUGUCAAAAGCAAACCUUAUGUUCCUUCCACUGUCCCCUGCUUCCUUGCCCUUCAGAAAGGUCUUGGAAACAGGGGCCAGAGGAUGUGGUAGCCACUUCACUGGUGUUCUGUGUCUGAAUGGGACUUUCUCACAGGCAGGCCAUGCUGGGACCUCAGCCAUGGGGGUGGCCAGGGAGGUGGUUGAGCAGAAGGAUAGCUGGGGACACUGACUGGGGGUAGAGUCACCCAGUGUCUUUAGACAUCCUGCUGUCUAAAGCACUGUGUCCAAAGGGUAUGGCACACUUAUAUGGACAGGUCACCAUUCCAAACAAGGAGGCCCAGUGUGUCAAUAGGAGAGGUCCUAAAGCAACAAAAAGGGCGGGGUGUCUUGGAUGGGCUUCAGGAAGGGAAAGACCAUUGUGUCUGGAGCUCAGAGAAUGGGGGCUGGUGUUUGAGAUGAGGCUGGAGAUUGGGCAUGGCAUCCUCACGCAUGUUAAGGAAUUGGGGACUUUAUCCUUAACAUCCUGGAAGCCAGUGAUCCCAUGGAGAGUGAGAAGAUCUGAUCUGUGUUUCAAAGGUCACUUGACUGCCGAGCAGCUGGAGGCGAGUUGCUCCUUUAGGAGACUGCUGCAGUUGCCUGGGUGAGAGGCUAGAGGGGUCUGGUCUAUAGCAGUGGCAGGGGAGAUGGAAAGAAGAGAAUGAUUUGAGGGGCAUUCGGGGGGCAAAAUCAACAGGACCUGGGGGGAGACGAAGGGAUCAAGAAUGAUGCCCAGAUUCUGGGUGAGUGGCAGUGCUGUGGUGCACAAGUAGUGAUGUUAUGUUUCCGGGUGACCUGCUGUUUAGCAGGAGCCCAGCCUGUGGCUAAGAAGUAUAGAGAACUGAAACUAGCUCCCUAGGGAUGGGAAAACCAAGUGGGCUGAGGAUAAGAACAGGGCCCCAGGGCUGGGUGCAGUCGCUCACGCCUGUAAUCUUAGCACUUUGGGAGGCCGAGGUGGGCGGAUCACUUGAGGUCAGGAGUUCGAAACCAGCCUGAUCAACACAGUGAAACCCCGUCUCUACCAAAAAAUACAAAAAUUACCCGGACAUGGUGGCACAUGCCUGUAGUUCCAGCGCCUUGGGAGGCUGAGGCAUGAGAAUUUCUUGAACCCGGGAGGUGGAGGUUGCAGUGAGCUGAGAUUGCCACUGCACUCCAGCCUGGGCAACACAGUGAGACCCUGUCUCAAAAAAAAAAAAAAAAAAAAGAAUAGGGUCCCAGGCUCAGCAGGUAGGGACACUGAGGUAAAAUCCUAUUCCCUAGGACUAGGGACUAGGAAGGGAGAAAAUAGGAAGCUGCUGUGGCAUAGGCAUCUGCAUGGGCAGAUGGUGAGGCCAAAGCCCCUGAUUUUGCCAUACCUCCUGCCCUGGUCAGGACUGGUUCAGGCAUUAGGGCAGGCCCAGCCAGGGCAGAAGCCUUCCUAGAUACACCUGUGGGGAGUUGAGGAACUACAGCAGGGCUGAAACCCUGCUUUCAGGGGCCCCCAUGUGGCUGGUAGGGGCAGCUUUUGGAAGCUAGACUGGAUCCUAUUACUCCCCAGAUGAAAAGUUCAAAUUCCUUAAUACAACUCAGAGCUCAUCACAAUGUCACAACCCUCCUUUCUCGGCUCGCUUCCUCCUUAAGAGCUCUGGGGCGAUUCUUUCAGACCAGCCUGAGGGAUCUUCCACAGGUUGUUAAUAGGGCUAGAAACAAAAAGUGGUGGUGUUUCUAUGAUCUAAUUUGUUGGAACAAACGUAGUGUUAAACUCAAACAUUUCUGUAGGAUUUCUUGGAGCUUUAACUAUACUAACAUUUACUGUAACUCUUCAGGACAGGGUAUGAUUACGUAUUUCCCACAUUUCUUUGGUCAGAGAACCCGUUUUUGUGAGGAGCAUUUCAUGGGACAGCUGUUGUGAGAAACAGUUUGGGAAGGGCUGUGUUGGUCCCAUGGAGGGGCUGGCUGUUCCCAGAGCAGGUCACUCCCCCACUUGCAUUGCCUUGCCUGGACUCUUUUCUUGGAGGGAGGUCCCUUUCCUCUACCCAUCUGAAUUUUUUUUUCUUCCACCAGUGUCCAGCUUGCCUUUCACCAUGGGCCUAAUGAUGGAAAUUACAGUUAUUUUGUAUCUUCAAACAGAACCAAGCAAAUCCUCUGAGCUUCAUUCAUAUGGGAAAUUUUCUUUCUUUCUUUUUUUUUUUUUUGAGAUGGAAUUUCGCUCUUGUUGCCCAGGCUGGAGUGCAAUGGCUCAAUCUCGGCUCACUGCAACCUCCACCUCCCAGGUUCAAGAGUUUCUCCUGCCUCAGCAGGAGGAUUACUGUAAUCCCAAGUAGCUGGGAUUACAGGCCUGCGCCACCACGACUAGCUAAUUUUGUACUUUUAGUAGAGAUGCGAUUUCACCAUGUUGGCUAGGCUGGUCUCGAACUCCUGACCUCAGGUGAUCCACCCUCCUCAGCCUCCCAAAGUGCUGGGAUUACAGGCAUGAGCCACAGUGCCGGACAUUAUGGGAAAAUUUUUUGAGGGACUAAACUAAUCUCCACAAAUAGCAAUGCAUUUAGGAAAUAUAUUUAAAGGGGAAAAAAAGACUCAUAGUUUCACUCAGUCAUGUUCAUAAUUUUUAGUAUUUGGGUUUUUUAGCAUGUAAUUUGUGUACAUAGUUUUGGUUUUUGUAAACUUGCAUAGGGGUUUUCUGGUACAAACUGGAAAACCUGCUAGACAAAUUCUGAAACAUCUGUAAUGCUUGUAGGUAGUUGUUGUAACACUAUGCCCACACAUAAUCACUUUCCAUAUUGCUGCAUAGUCUUUGUAACCAUUUUUCUUCUUCUUUUUUUUGAGAUGGAGUUUUGCUCUUGUUGCCCAGGCUGGAGUGCAAUGGCGCGAUCUUGGCCCACUGCAACCUCUGCCUCCCGGGUUCAAGCUAUUCUGCUGCCUUAGCCUCCCGAGUAGCUGGGAUUACAGGCACACGCCACCACGCCCGGCUAGUUUUUGUAUUUUUAGUAGAGACGGGGUUUCACCAUGUCAGCCAGGCUUUUCUUGAACUUCUGAUCUCAAGUGAUCCUCACUCCUCAGCCUCCCAAAUUGCUGGGAUUACAGGCGUGAGCCACCACGCCCACCUGUAACCAUUAUUUUUAAGAUUGCUACCAUUGGAUAGUUCUGUCAUGGUCCAACUUUUGGAUAUUUAAAAUUGAUCCCUGUGUGGCUAACAGAAUUAAUGUUUCCAAAAAUGUUGAAAAUUAUAUAGUUCUCUUAAUUCCCCACCUCUAACUAUAUUUUUGGGUUAUUUCUUUAGGAACAGAUGCCCAGGAGUCAUAUUACUGAGAAUCUAGAAAUCUUUUGCAAAGUUCUUGUUAUAUUGCCAAAUUGCUUCCCAAAAGGGUUGUUCUAAACCAUAAUUUCACCAGCAAUGUAGGGGAGAACCAUUUUUAUGCUGCCCUUGUGAGAAUUGGGUAUGAAAACAUUUUUAAAAUGAUUUUUGAUGAGGUGAAAAUAAUAUUUGAAUAUAUUUUAAUUUGCCUUUCCCCCACUUAUAGUGAGCUUAAACAUUUUUUCCUUUUCCUAGCUGUAUUUCUCCCUUUGUUAUUCGUUCUUUCGUCCAUUUAUCUACUGGGGAGAUGGGGAGUGUUAUCUUUUUAGUUUAUCAGUUAUUUGCAUUUUAAAUAUAACCAUUUGCCAUAUUUUAACAACGAUUUUUCCAUUAAAUAAUUCUUUUUAUAAAAAAACUUUAUAUAUCUGUUGAUGUUUUGUGAUUUUUAUUGCUUCUAAGCUAAUACAGAUUUUUGGAUCUUAUUCAAUUUCGCUUUCUUCUGUUUAGGUUAUUAUCUGGUUUUAUACCUAACUACUUAUUUUCAAAUUGCUAACCAGUUAUCCUAAUAGUAUUUACUGAAUUCCUUCCCACUCCUACAUCACAUAUUAAAAUUAUUUUAUGCCUAAAUUAUUUAUAAUAUUUCAGUUAUUCUUCCUAUAAUUACAAUUUGAACCAUCAAAGUAGGUUUUCAUAGUUGGCAGAGCUAGUUCUUCUUCAUAAUUCUGUUUCAGAAUUUUCUUUGAUAUUCUUCCUCAACAUUUUAAACAUUUUGUCAAGUUUCAGUGCAACUGACUUUUGGUUUUUAUUUAUUUAAAAACUGGGCCAUGCCGGGCGCAGUGGCUCACGCCUGUAAUCCCAGCACUUCGGGAGACUGAGAUGGGUGAAUCACUUGAGGUCAGGAGUUUGAGACCAGACUGGCCAAUGUGGUGAAACCCCAUCUCUACUAAAAAUACAAAAAUUUGCUGGGCAUGGUGGCAUGUGCCUGUAAUCCCAGCUACUGGGGAGGCUGAAGCAGGAGAAUUGUUUGAACCCGGGAGACGGAGGUUGCAGUGAGCCAAGAUUGUGCCACUGCACUCCAGCCUGGGCAACAGAGUGAGACUCCAUCUCAAACAAACAAACAAACAAACAAACAAAAAACUGGACUAGGCGUGGUGGCGGUUUGGGAGACUGAGGCUGGAGGAUUGCCUGAGGCCAGCAGUUUGAGGUUACAGUGAGGUAUGACUGUGCCACUGCACUCCAACCUGGGUAAGACCCUAUCUCUGAAAAACAAACAAGCAAACCCCAGAACUCUGGCUGCAAAAGUAGUACAUAUUUCUUUGAAGGAAAAAAAGGAAAACUUGAUAAUCCUACCACCCAAAGAUGUUUUUAAAUCACUUAUGUGGUACUCAGUUAUGUGCCAUGCACUGUCCAAGUGCUUACAAAUAUUAUACUAACUCCCUUUGUGUUUAUAACAACUGUCUGAAGUCAGUAGACUCAUUUUCCAGUUUUCCAGUUUAGGAAACUGAUAUUACACCUUUUCUACAGAUGGGGAAACUUGCCCAGGGUGCCCAGGCAGUCCGCAGAACCAUGCUUUGAAUCAGGGCAGUGUGGUUCCAGGGUCCUGUACAGAUCAAACACCCUGACUCUGCCAUUCCAUCAGAUACAUGAUUCAUAUUUUGGUGUAUUUGCCUCCAAUCUUGAGCAAAGUGGGUUGUCCCUGUACAUACUUUGUGUAAUCUUUUAGCUUAACAGGUGUCAUGAACACUUCCGUAUCAUAAAUCUUUCCCAGCAUGAUUUUUAUUAUCUAUUUAAUAUUUCUCAUAUUCAAUGUAGAACAAUGCACUUAACCAAUUUCUCAUUUUUGUAAUAAUUUUCUUCCCAUUUUCCCCUGUAAUAACACUGCUGAGAUAUAUAUUUUUUUCUUCUUUUUUUUACUGUUCUGAAGAUACUCUGGCAGAAAUGUAUGUUCCUCAGGCUAAAUCUUUUCACACAUCCACAAUCAUUUUAUCAUAAAUUCUAGAGCUGGAAA